AGCUACAGCAGCGGCGCGGAGACUGCGGGGCGGGCCAUGGCGGCGAACCUGAGCCGGAACGGGCCAGCGCUGCAAGAGGCCUACGUGCGGGUGGUCACCGAGAAGUCCCCGACCGACUGGGCUCUCUUUACCUAUGAAGGCAACAGCAAUGACAUCCGCGUGGCUGGCACAGGGGAGGGUGGCCUGGAGGAGAUGGUGGAGGAGCUCAACAGCGGGAAGGUGAUGUACGCCUUCUGCAGAGUGAAGGACCCCAACUCUGGACUGCCCAAAUUUGUCCUCAUCAACUGGACAGGCGAGGGCGUGAACGAUGUGCGGAAGGGAGCCUGUGCCAGCCACGUCAGCACCAUGGCCAGCUUCCUGAAGGGGGCCCAUGUGACCAUCAACGCACGGGCCGAGGAGGAUGUGGAGCCUGAGUGCAUCAUGGAGAAGGUGGCCAAGGCUUCAGGUGCCAACUACAGCUUUCACAAGGAGAGUGGCCGCUUCCAGGACGUGGGACCCCAGGCCCCAGUGGGCUCUGUGUACCAGAAGACCAAUGCCGUGUCUGAGAUUAAAAGGGUUGGUAAAGACAGCUUCUGGGCCAAAGCAGAGAAGGAGGAGGAGAACCGUCGGCUGGAGGAAAAGCGGCGGGCCGAGGAGGCACAGCGGCAGCUGGAGCAGGAGCGCCGGGAGCGUGAGCUGCGUGAGGCUGCACGCCGGGAGCAGCGCUAUCAGGAGCAGGGUGGCGAGGCCAGCCCCCAGAGCAGGACGUGGGAGCAGCAGCAAGAAGUGGUUUCAAGGAACCGAAAUGAGCAGGGGUCAACAUGUGCUUCCCUCCAGGAGUCUGCCGUGCACCCGAGGGAGAUUUUCAAGCAGAAGGAGAGGGCCAUGUCCACCACCUCCAUCUCCAGUCCUCAGCCUGGCAAGCUGAGGAGCCCCUUCCUGCAGAAGCAGCUCACCCAACCAGAGACCCACUUUGGCAGAGAGCCAGCUGCUGCCAUCUCAAGGCCCAGGGCAGAUCUCCCUGCUGAGGAGCCGGCGCCCAGCACUCCUCCAUGUCUGGUGCAGGCAGAAGAGGAGGCUGUGUAUGAGGAACCUCCAGAGCAGGAGACCUUCUACGAGCAGCCCCCACUGGUGCAGCAGCAAGGUGCUGGCUCUGAGCACAUUGACCACCACAUUCAGGGCCAGGGGCUCAGUGGGCAAGGGCUCUGUGCCCGUGCCCUGUACGACUACCAGGCAGCCGACGACACAGAGAUCUCCUUUGACCCCGAGAACCUCAUCACGGGCAUCGAGGUGAUCGACGAAGGCUGGUGGCGUGGCUAUGGGCCGGAUGGCCAUUUUGGCAUGUUCCCUGCCAACUACGUGGAGCUCAUUGAGUGAGGCUGAGGGCACAUCUUGCCCUUCCCCUCUCAGACAUGGCUUCCUUAUUGCUGGAAGAGGAGGCCUGGGAGUUGACAUUCAGCACUCUUCCAGGAAUAGGACCCCCAGUGAGGAUGAGGCCUCAGGGCUCCCUCCGGCUUGGCAGACUCAGCCUGUCACCCCAAAUGCAGCAAUGGCCUGGUGAUUCCCACACAUCCUUCCUGCAUCCCCCGACCCUCCCAGACAGCUUGGCUCUUGCCCCUGACAGGAUACUGAGCCAAGCCCUGCCUGUGGCCAAGCCCUGAGUGGCCACUGCCAAGCUGCGGGGAAGGGUCCUGAGCAGGGGCAUCUGGGAGGCUCUGGCUGCCUUCUGCAUUUAUUUGCCUUUUUUCUUUUUCUCUUGCUUCUAAGGGGUGGUGGCCACCACUGUUUAGAAUGACCCUUGGGAACAGUGAACGUAGAGAAUUGUUUUUAGCAGAGUUUGUGACCAAAGUCAGAGUGGAUCAUGGUGGUUUGGCAGCAGGGAAUUUGUCUUGUUGGAGCCUGCUCUGUGCUCCCCACUCCAUUUCUCUGUCCCUCUGCCUGGGCUAUGGGAAGUGGGGAUGCAGAUGGCCAAGCUCCCACCCUGGGUAUUCAAAAACGGCAGACACAACAUGUUCCUCCACGCGGCUCACUCGAUGCCUGCAGGCCCCAGUGUGUGCCUCAACUGAUUCUGACUUCAGGAAAAGUAACACAGAGUGGCCUUGGCCUGUUGUCUUCCCCUAUUUUCUGUCCCAGCUCAUCCGUGUCUCUGAAGAACAAAUAUGCUUUUGGACCACGAAUUCCCAGUUUGGUCUACACAGGCUCGCAGCUCUCACCUGUCCUGCUGUAGCCUGAAUGCUCCCAUGUGGGAAUAGCACCCCACCACCUGCCCAGUGUCUGCCUCUGCUCCGUGUCUGGGGUGAGCACCCUCACCCUGAGACUGUGGCUGAUGAUGAUCAGCCACCAGGAAGAGGCUAAAUGUUAAGAUGGGACUGAAGUUGGAGCCUUCCUGCGUUCCAGUUCCUCUAGGAGAGGCCAAGGGCUGCCCUGCUCCCAGCUUCAGGGAGCCUCUGCCUACAUGGGAUGGCCCACUGUGUGGCGUCAGGUACCUGGCACCCACUGAGCAUCCGGGGAAUUAGGUCCCUCCUGUGCCCCAGAGCUGCUAGGCAGACUGCUAGGCGGUUGACUCAAGGUGUUACCUGCUAGUGCCUGGGGUGAAGGCUGCAUGGAGCCCAACCUUGCUCCUGGCCUUCCUGUGCUCAGGCCUCUCCCCUUUUCGCCAGGGCUUCCUGGUGCCUCUCCCAUGAAGAGGGAACUUCCCCUCCACUCCCAUGGAAGACCCAGGUUUGGGCUGUUGCCAGCUUUGAGGCCCCCUGUGGGCUUGCCUGUCCCAACCCAAGAGGCAGGGCUCAAAGUGCCACCCGGGGGUUGCAAGGACAGCAGAGGACCACCUGCCCUCUGCAGGAAGCUGUCCAGGAAGCCGUGUCCUGGGCUGUGGUCCUUGCUCCCCAUGGGGAGAGCUGGGUCACUUGGCCUCUUCUAACUGGCCCCAAGCACGCCAAUUCUGGAGCAUGGUUACUAAGUGGCUCUGAAGCUUCAGGGUCACCACAGGCUUGUCCUGACUGCAAACUCAUGGAGUGGUUGCAGCCCUGGCUCAGUGUCCUGAUGACUAGGUGUGGGUACUAGGCUCCUGCCCCUGGUGACACACGUAUGGAGUGGGGGAGGGUGGGUGGCUGCACCCCUGGUUCUGGAGUCCCCACAGCUGAUGGCGGUGUGAGCCUGGCAUGCACGGCUGCGCUGGACUCCAGGCUGUUGGGGGAGGUGCCUUUAUUGCCCAAGCCCACCCCUCACUUGGCCUUGCCCUGGGCAGCCACAGCCUCCAUGGCCUUCCGCACCGUUUCCUCAUCACCCAGGAACUGCAUGGGCUUGGUGGGCUUCAGCUCCUUGUUCAGCUCAUACACAAUGGGGAUCCCCGUGGGCAGGUUCAGCUCCAUGAUCGCCUGGUCUGACAUCCCUAUGCCGGAAGGAAUAGGUGUCCUUAGCCCCUCUGUCCCCAGCCUGUUUACACAGCAGACACUAUGUGACCUUUAUGGUCCACAGAGCCAGUUCCCCUGGCACCAAUUCCUUCCCAGCCCUGAGAACGAGGCCACAGAAAUGUUGCCAAAGGUCAAGGAGUAACUGAGUUAGACCAAGCAGCCUACAGAAAUAGCCCAGUGGUGAAAAAAAUGGGGACUUCAGCCCCACCCAAGUGGCUGUGAUCUGUGGUGGUGCUGUCCAUAGUUCCCUCAGCCCAGUGUGACUCCAGCCAGACUGAAGUUGAGGGUCAGGAAGGGACACUCACCCUUUGUUUUUUUUUUUUCUUUUCUUUUUCUUUUUCUUUUUUUUGAGAUGGAGUUUUACUCCUCUUGCCCAGGCUGGAGUGCAGUGGCACGAUCUUGGCUCACUGCAACCUCCAUCUCCUGGGUUGAAGUGAUUCUGCCUCAGCCUCCCAAGUAGCUGGGAUUACAGGUGAGCGCCACCACACCCGGCUAAUUUUGUAUUUUUAGUAGAAACGGGUUUUACCAUGUUGGUCAGGCUGGUCUCAAACUCCUGACCUCAGGUGAUCUGCCUGCCUCAGCCUCCCAAAGUGCUGGGAUUACAGGAGUGAGCCACCGUGCCCAGCACCCUUUGGUUUCUAAAGUGCUCUAAAUUCUAGACAUCCUGAACAGAGGAGCAAGUGCGGAAUGGAGCUGGAGGAGGGACAGGGAGGCCGAGCCUGGUCGAAACCUGACCCUGCCUGCCUCCUGCAGCCCCUGAGCUGGGAAUAGCAGCUCGACCUUUGAUGUUCGCGCCACUCCACCCCUGCUCCGUGCAGGAGGGUUUAAGAAAAUGUUCUCUGGGGAGUCAGAGUGAAAUCCCUCAUAUUCACCACCAAAAGUGCGUCCCCUUUCCCCAAACCAGGCUGUGGGAGGGUCAUGGGGCUGCAUGAAGUCUCCGGAAGGGAGAGGAGGCAGGUGGUCCUUCCCUCUGCCUGGCCCCAGUGCCAGGUGCCAGGUGUCCGUGUUUGGAGCGGGCAGGCUUGGGGCUGGCUGGGUCUCCGGGGCCUGCCGGUCUGGGUGCUCUGGCCAACUGCCCAACGGCCCUAGGAGCAGGAGGUCUGGGGCACACCCUUCUAGCCUUUCCAGGACUCAACAAGCUUUAAGGUCAUUCAGAUGCUAAUUUAGACUGCCCUUGUGUCAGAAUACUAAGGUGGGAGGCGGAGCGGAGGUGCCAGUCACUCUGGGCGAGGCCUUACUGCGCCCAUGCAUCCCGGGCCCAUUUGUCAGCCCUUGCUCUUCAGUGGGAGCCCAGCUGCAAGCCCAGAGUCUGGCCACUCCAUAGUCCUGCACCCCUCUUUUGAUUGGUCUUUCCUUUGCCCAGAGAGGGGCUCCAGAGGGAGAUAGGUGGUGAAGCUCAUGCAGGGAUUCUGAGGACCUGAUGGGGGAGGGCCCUGCGAGGGGUCCAAGCCUACAUCAAGAGGAAUUCAGUACCAGGGGGAGCUCCCCACCACCCCGGAAAAGGGAGAGGCCCAGAGAUGGAGGUGGCUUGUCCAGGGCCCCACAGUAAGUUGGGAUUUGGAGCCAGAUGCUCUAAGCCCAGCCCUUCCGUUUCCUAGCUGGGUGUCCCUUGGCAGAUGCCACCUUUGGAGCCUGCCCCACCUCGGGACACAGCGAGCUUCGAGUGCAGUCAGCCCCUGUGGAGUGUGUCCCAGUUACACAGAAAUGGGGAAAAUUUCACAAAACUAAAAAAUGGCUUCUCAGCCCUCCUUUUUCAGUGAAUGAUGUGGAGCCCCACGCCUAGAAAGCCUGGUCCAUGGGCGAGAGACUUUGCUGAGAUGAGAAGCCAGCUGGGGCUGCUGCCCACCCACCCUGCCCAGGCUCCUGAAGGUGGCCUCACCUUCCAGGUGCUUGACAAUGCCCCGCAGGCUGUUCCCGUGGGCUGCAAUGAGCACUCGCUUGCCGGCCUUGAUCUGGGGAACAAUCUCCUCGUUCCAGAAGGGCAGGGCCCGGGCAAUGGUGUCCUUGAGGCUCUCGCAGGUGGGGAGUUCCCCGGGCUUCAGGCCUGCGUACCGACGCUCCUGGGGGACACAGGCACGCUGCUUUCCCUCCCAAGCCAGUGGGCCCCCACCCGACUCCCCACUCUGCAGCUUCCCAGAGGCCUUCCCAGCAAAGGCAGCCCACCUUGCUAAUGGAGUUGUAGUAGGGGUGCUUCUCGUCCAUCGGGGGCGGCGGGAUGUCGAAGGAGCGCCUCCAGAUCUUCACCUGCUCCUCCCCGUGCUUGGCGGCCGUUUCUGCCUUGUUGAGGCCUGUGAGGCCCCCGUAAUGCCGCUCAUUGAGGCGCCAAGUGCGCACCACAGGCAGCCACAUCUGGUCCGUGCCGUCCAGGAUGGCCCAGAGGGUGCGGAUGGCCCGCUUCAGCACUGACGUGUAGCAGAUGUCAAACUCCAUCUUGGCAUCCUUGAUGGCCUUGGCUCCCCGCUUGGCCUCCUCGGUCCCCUUUUCACUCAGCUCUGCAUCGAACCAGCCACAGAAACGGUUCUCCUGGUUCCAUGUGCUCUCGCCGUGCCGGACCAUCACGAGGCGGUGAGUGGCCAUGGUGGCAGCAGGGACCACAGAGGACUCUGGACGGGGACGGCUGCUUCCCAACACUCCCAGCUUUAUAAUAGUGUCUUCCCAGCCCCCACCCACCCCAGCCAACUGCCAAUCAGCAUUCCAGGCGGUGGCAGGUGACCAGUAGCUGAGCUGCUGGGGGCUGGGGGCCAGGGGAGUGUGCAGGCCAAGAGGCUGUGCUUAAAAUAGCCCCACGCAUCCACCAGCUCCUGGCCUGGGUUCAGGUGGCAUGUCUAUAACCAGCUGGCACCCAGAGCCCAGACUGAGUGGGGCUGCUGGUCAGGGAUGGGCGUGAAGGGCAGAAGUCUGGGCCAGGGGAGAUGGGGAUAGCAGGGACAGAGGGGCUCUCCAGGGCAACGCUCAGUGGCCUAUCAGCCAUUCUCUGCUCAGACAGAGGCACAAACAAAAUCCCAACCCCUUUCUCCUGUGAUUGGCAGCCAGGCUAGGAGGCGGCCCUCAGCAGGCAGAGGAGGAGAGCCAGAGGAGCUGGUGCAGACCACAGCUUUGUGGAGAGGAGUCUGGCCUUGUGGAAGGUACCAGGCAGCAGCAGCAGAAUGGGCAAGGGCUGGGGCUGAGCCGGGUUUCCAGGACAAAGGGGGAAAGGGCCCCUGUCUUUCCUCCGGGGUCCCUUUGUCAAGGUCUCAUCCAUACAUGCCCCAUGCUCCCACCCUAUCUGCCCUCACCCAAGCCACGCUCACUCUCCUAGCCGAAACCACCUUGAAAAAGAGAAAUCCAAGGGGGUUUGGGGGCAGGACUGAGGACUGUCAGAAGUCUUGAUUGUUAGGUAAAUGCUCAGCUUAGCAGGAACCCACAACGUAGGCUGAAGGGUGGCACGGAGUUGAGUCUAGGACCAAGACUUCUGCAUUCAGGUUUGGGGGAUGAGAGCCACCAAGGCAGGGAAGAGACUAUGAGCAAUAAAGUCACAAUUGGGGCCCUAAUGAAGGGGCCAUGGCCAGACCCUUGGGCAUGGGCCCCAUCCAGGGCCUCCCAUUUCCUCCCACCCCAGUGACCACACUGUCACCUGCGACACUUCUGAUAACAGGAGCGGGUAGGUGAGAGGCCAGCAGAGGGACCACCACUCUGAGACUUGGAUCUGAGUGUGCAAGAAACCCUCGACAGGCCUCCCUCCAUCCCUGCUGGCCUACCUGGGGAGGGGCUCCUGGCUUGGGGCCUGUGAAGCUAAGGCUCUGUACCCAAAGGUUGGCAGACAAGUCCCAGUGGGCAAAGUCCUGUCGGCUGCCAGGACCCCCAAGGCUGGCAGGUGGAACCCAUCCCUCCUAGCAGUGCCAUGCGCAGGUCUCACUGUUCCACACUGAUCCUGAUUGAAGCCACAUCUCCUCAUCUGCUUUUGUCCCUUUGACCAAGAGUUGAUUCACUAGCCCAACUAAACAUGACUGAGGACCAGGCUCUGGCAGUCCCACAGGGGCCAGACAUGAAGCCCAUAUUUCAGUGGAGGAGGGAUCGUACCAGCAGCUAAACAUGCCUACCGUAGAUAGCACCAGAUGCUAGGAAGGAAGGACCAUAAUGUACUGGGAGAGAUGGGAAAGGAGAGGCCGGGGACAGCCCUGAGGUGACAUGUGAGUGGAAAGAGCGGAGUGCAAAGGCCUCAGCUAUGAUGAGUCCUACAGGGAGAGCAAUUCAGGUAGAGGGGUUGGCAAAGACCCAAGCCCUACAGAAAGCAAACAAGCUGGGGCAGCGACCAUCAGGGGCACAUGGCAGAGAGGUGGGCUUUGUGUCCCAACACAGUGGGAAUCACUGGAGACUUUGAAGCAUGGUCAUAUUUUCAAGUCACUUGCAGCUGUGUAGGAGUGGAAGUAGAAGCUGAGUACCCUGCAGGUCUCGGCAGCUUUGAUGAGAACAAGGCCGCUUAGCCAGGGCUGGGUGCAGAAGCAGUGGCAAGGAUCCCCCAGACCUGGGAGACCUCACUGCCAACCAAGCAGGAGGUGUCAAAAAGGAAAGGGGAGCCCAAAGAAGGGCUGGACUUCGGGGAAGCAAGCCCCUGCUUCUGACCCUUGGCUCCGGCUUGACUUUCCUUUGAUUCAUUUGACAAGUAGUUGCUGGCCUCUGCAGUGUGCCAGAGCUUUCUUGGAGGGGUACAGGGGUAGGAAAACCAAAAGCCACCCUCAGGGCCUCCAUCCAGGAAGGCAUAGCAUGGUGGGCGGCGAGGAAGGCUGCUGAGUCAACAAGGUGGUCCCAGGAAGGUGGAGGGAGCAUCUUCCCAUGUCUCUCCCACUGACAGCCACCAAUCCUGGACAGAUGCAGGAGCAGCUGUCAGUAGACAGAUAAGAAAAGGAGAUCAGAUUCAAAGUUCCGCAGAGAAGUGGUGAGGUAACAAGUAUUGCCUAGCCUGGACACACAGGCGGCUUGAAACCUCAAGUGCACCAACAGAAAGAGCUCCAGGAAGAAUCAGAGGAGUGGGAUGUGAAGCCCCUCGAAGUCAGUGAGUUGGGGGAAUCCCUCCAAUUUUUCUUUUCUUCUCUACCCCAGCUCCUGGGCAGUAACAUGGAGGUGGCAGUGGUGGCACAGUGACGGUAGUGUGAGCUGGGUACGCACUUGAAACCUGAGAGGGUAACGCUACCCUCUGUCUAGAGGAGCCAUGGCCCCAAAAGCAUGGGGCAACCACCUUCUGCAGCUCCUUUCUGCCCCCCUGCGCUGGGCCCUGGAUGCAGUUUCAGGGAGUAUGCAGCAGGGUAGGUAGGGAAAGAGCCCCAGAUUUGUGGCUGGAGGUCUUGGUAGGGAUGUUGCAGGGAGCUGUUGUGUUUCAGGGAGAGUACAGAGAAGGGAGAGAUGAAGUGAGUGAUCCGAUAAAGUGAUAUGUGAAGUCAUUGGCUUGCUGCCAAGCUGCGCACAGGGCUGACCCUAGAUGCACAUUGCAGGUCCCAGACUGACCGGUGUAGAUACAGGACUAAUAUGACUAGUAGUGCAAACACUUUAAACAGUCAACAUUCUGCUUAGGAUUUAAACAAGGUCCAGAGUCUCAACAUAAUAUUUAAAAUAUCCAGGUUAUCCAAAAUAACCCAGUGUAUGAAAACCAGGAAAAUCUUAACAUGGGAGAAAAGAAGAUGAUCAAUACAUGCCCAUCCUGAGAUGAUUCAACUAUUGGAAUGAUCAGAUACAGACUUCAAAGCAGCUAUUUAUAACCAGCCUUCAGAAAGUAUUGGUGAAUAUUCUUAAACAGAAUGGAAAUGACAAAGCAUGGAGUCCAUAAAUUAGAUGAUAGUUUGGAAAAAGAUAUAAACUUACAAACCAAGAAGCUCAGUGAACCACACAACUGGAUAAAUUAACAACAAAAGUCCAAGCUUAGACACAUCAUAAAGAAACUUCUGAAAACUAAAGACCAAGAAAAAUAAGAUCAGCCAGAGAAAAACGAUACAUUUCAUUCAGGUGAACAAUUCUUUGAAAGACUGGAUCUUCACCAGAAACUAUAGAGGCCAGAAAGAAGUGGAACAUUUUUAGUUUUGAAAUAACUGUCACCCAAGAAUUCUAUAUCCAGUAAAAAUUUCUAUUUUACUGGAAUAAAAGAAUGAAAUAAAGACAUUCUCAAAUGAAGGCAAGCUGAGGAAAUUCAUAACCAAAGAAUCUGCUUUAAAAAAAUGUUAAACCAAGUUCUUCAGACAGAAGAGAUUACUGGGGGCAAUUCAAAACUUUGGGAAUGCAGGAAGAACAUCAUAAAUGGCAAAAGUCCACAUAAAUAUGAAACUAUUCUUUACUUCUUUAAGAGUUAUGUGAUGGUUGAAUUAAGUCAUGAUACUGUCUGAUGGAGGCUUCAGUGUAUACAGAUGUAAGACAACUAGAACAUGAGGGGAGAAGGGUGAAGGGACCUAGAUGGUAGUGAGGUUUCUACAUGCUACUUGAAAUGGCAAAACAUUAAUCUAAAUUGACUGUAAGAGUAUGUGUAUUUGGCCGGGCAGG